GAGGCUUUGCGGUGGCUGUUGGCUUGGCGGUGGUCGCUUGGCUUGGCGUGGCAGUGAUCGCUUGGCUUGGCAUUUCUGGCUUGGCGGUCCUCCUUUCGCAGAUUGGAAACCGCGGGCUAUCCUGCUGGGAGGUUGUGGCCGAGGCAGUAGCUCGCUACUGAUGGCCUCCUGGGGUGGAGAAAAGCGGGGAGGGGCUGAGGGGUCUCCGAAGCCGGCAGUCUACGCCACGAGGAAGACCCCUAGCGUCGGGAGCCAGGGGGACCAGUGGUACUUGGGCUACCCGGGGGACCAGUGGUCCUCGGGCUUCCCCUACAGCUGGUGGAAAAACAGCGUCGGCAGCGAGAGCAAGCACGGUGAGGGCGCCUUAGACCAGCCCCAGCACGACGUCCGCCUGGAAGAUCUUGGCGAGCUCCACAGAGCUGCCCGGUCGGGCGACGUCCCUGGGGUGGAGCACAUCUUAGCUCCUGGAGACACUGGCGUGGACAAGAGGGAUAGGAAGAAGAGCAUUCAGCAACUAGUUCCUGAAUAUAAGGAAAAACAGACACCUGAAAGUCUUCCUCAAAAUAACAAUCCAGAUUGGCAUCCUACUAAUUUGACCCUUAGUGAUGAGACUUGUCAGAGAUCCAAGAAUCUGAAAGUUGAUGAUAAAUGUCCAUCUGUAUCACCAUCAAUGCCUGAAAAUCAGUCAGCAACCAAAGAACUGGGACAGAUGAACUUAACAGAACGAGAAAAGAUGGACACUGGAGUUGUACUUCUCUCAGGGAAUGAUACUCUCCAUGACCUGUGCCAAUCACAGCUACCAGAAAACAAAGAGAGCAAAGAAGCAGAACAAGACUCGGAGCUGACAUCAGAGGAAGAGCAAGAAAGACUUAAAGGAUGCGAAAAUAAGCAGCCACAGAAAACGUCUCAAGAACCAGAAAUGGCUAAGGAUUGCGAUAGAGAGGAUAUACCUAUAUAUCCAGUACUUCCUCAUGUGCAAAAAUCUGAGGAAAUGUGGAUUGAACAAGGCAAAUUAGAGUGGAAAAACCAAUUAAAACUCGUCAUAAAUGAGUUAAAGCAGAGGUUUGGUGAAAUUUAUGAAAAAUACAAAAUUCCGGCUUGUCCUGAGGAAGAGCCACUACUUGAUAACUCUACAAGAGGAACAGAUGUAAAGGAUAUUCCCUUUAAUUUGACAAAUAACAUACCUGGUUGUGAGGAAGAAGAUGCAUCUGAAAUAUCUGUCUCAGUGGUAUUCGAGACAUUUCCUGAACAAAAAGAACCCAGUCUCAAAAAUAUCAUCCAUCCAUACUAUCAUCCAUACUCUGGGUCCCAGGAACAUGUUUGCCAGUCAUCUUCUAAGUUUCAUUUACAUGAAAAUAAAUUAGACUGCGACAAUGAUAACAAACCAGGCAUUGGACAUAUUUUUAGUACAGAUAAGAACUUUCAUAAUGAUGCAAGCACUAAGAAAGCAAGGAACCCAGAAGUGGUUAUGGUUGAAAUGAAAGAAGACCAAGAGUUUGAUUUGCAAAUGACAAAAAAUAUGAACCAAAAUAGUGACAGUGGCAGUACAAACAACUAUAAAAGCCUGAAACCUAAAUUAGAAAAUCUGAGUUCUUUACCACCAGAUUCUGACAGAACAUCAGAAGUAUAUCUACAUGAAGAAUUACAGCAAGACAUGCAAAAGUUUAAGAAUGAGGUCAACACAUUAGAAGAAGAGUUCCUGGCUUUGAAGAAAGAAGAUGUUCAACUUCAUAAAGAUGUUGAAGAAGAAAUGGAGAAGCACAGAAGUAAUAGCACAGAAUUAUCAGGAACCCUAACUGAUGGUACUACUGUUGGCAAUGAUGAUGAUGGACUAAAUCAGCAGAUUCCUAGGAAGGAAAAUGGAGAGCAUGACAGGCCUGCAGAUAAAACAUCUAAUGAAAAGAACGAGGUCAAAAACCAAAUAUAUCCUGAGGCUGACUUUGCUGACUCAAUGGAGCCAUCUGAAAUAGCCUCAGAGGAUUGUGAAUUGUCUCACUCUGUUUAUGAGAAUUUUAUGUUGCUGAUUGAACAACUUAGAAUGGAGUAUAAAGAUUCUGCUAGCCUACCAAGAAUCCAAGACACAUUUUGUUUGUGUGAACACUUACUGAAACUUAAGAAUAAUCACUGUGACCAACUUACAGUAAAACUUAAACAAAUGGAAAAUAUGGUCAGUGUACUACAAAAUGAGCUAUCUGAAACAAAAAAGACAAAAUUACAGUUAGAACUUCAAAAAAUUGAAUGGGAGAAAGAGCUGUACGAUUUGAGACUUGCCUUAAAACAAGAAAAUGAGGAGAAAAGAAAUGCCGAUAUGUUGUAUAAUAAAGAUAGUGAACAGUUAAGAAUAAAAGAAGAGGAGUGUGGGAAAGUGGUUGAAACAAAGCAACAACUUAAAUGGAAUCUGAGAAGACUUGUUAAGGAAUUGAGGACAGUAAGAAAUAACUUGGAUCUGGUUGUGCAGGAGAGAAACGAUGCCCAGAAGCAACUUUCUGAAGAACAGGAUGCCAGAAUAUUACAAGAUCAGAUUCUGACGAGUAAACAAAAGGAACUAGAAAUGGCUCGAAAGAAAAUGAAUUCUGAGAUUUCUCAUAGGCAUCAGAAAGAAAAGGAUCUCUUUCAUGAAGAUUGCAUGUUGCAGGAAGAAAUUGCCUUGCUGAGACUGGAAAUAGAUACAAUAAAAAAUCAGAACAAGCAAAAGGAAAAGAAAUAUUUUGAGGACAUUGAGGCUGUGAAAGAAAAGAAUGAUAACCUUCAAAAAAUUAUAAAACUAAAUGAGGAAACAUUAACAGAAACAAUACUCCAGUACAGUGGACAGCUGAACAAUCUGACAGCUGAGAACAAAAUACUCAAUUCUGAACUGGAGAAUGGGAAACAGAACCAAGAAAGACUAGAAAUAGAAAUGGAAUCAUACCGUUGUAGACUAGCUGCUGCUGUACGUGACUGUGAUCAAAGUCAGACAGCAAGAGACCUAAAACUUGAUUUCCAGAGAACAAGACAAGAGUGGGUUCGUUUACAUGACAAAAUGAAGGUUGAUAUGUCUGGCCUACAAGCUAAGAAUGAGAUUCUUUCUGAAAAACUUUCUAAUGCUGAAAGUAAAAUUAACAGCCUACAAAUUCAGCUCCAUAACACAAGAGAUGCUCUUGGAAGAGAGAGUUUGAUUUUGGAACGUGUGCAAAGAGACCUCAGCCAAACACAGUGUCAGAAGAAAGAAACUGAACAAAUGUACCAAAUUGAACAAAGCAAACUGAAGAAAUACAUUGCCAAGCAGGAAUCUGUAGAGGAGAGAUUAUCUCAACUACAAAGUGAAAAUAUGUUGCUUCGACAGCAACUGGAUGAUGCUCACAAGAAAGCUAACAGUCAAGAAAAGACAAGCAGUACUAUCCAAGACCAGUUUCAUUCUGCUGCCAAAAAUCUUCAAGCUGAGAGUGAAAAGCAGAUUCUUUCACUACAAGAGAAGAACAAGGAGCUGAUGGAUGAAUAUAAUCAUUUAAAAGAAAGAAUGGAUCAAUGUGAGAAAGAGAAAGCAGGAAGAAAAAUUGACCUUACAGAAGCACAGGAAACUGUACCUUCACGAUGUCUACAUCUGGAUGCAGAGAAUGAAGUUCUUCAACUUCAACAGACAUUAUUCUCUAUGAAAGCAAUACAAAAGCAAUGUGAAACACUACAGAAGAAUAAGAAGCAGCUGAAACAAGAAGUAGUAAACCUCAAAAGUUAUAUGGAAAGAAAUAUGUUAGAACGUGGUAAAGCUGAAUGGCAUAAACUGUUGAUUGAAGAAAGAGCAAGGAAGGAGAUAGAAGAAAAAUUAAACGAAGCCAUUCUCACCUUGCAGAAACAAGCAGCAGUAUCUCAUGAACAGUUAGUACAGUUAAGGGAGGAUAAUACUACUUCAAUAAAAACUCAGAUGGAACUCACAAUCAAAGAUCUGGAAUCUGAAAUCUCCAGAAUAAAAACUUCGCAAGCCGACUUUAAUAAAACCGAAUUGGAAAGAUAUAAGGAACUCUACCUAGAAGAAGUGAAAGUUAGAGAAUCCUUGUCAAAUGAACUCAGUAGAACUAAUGAGAUGAUAGCAGAGGUCAGUACGCAACUUACUGUGGAGAAAGAGCAGACCAGAUCCAGAUCUCUAUUCACUGCUUAUGCUACAAGGCCAGUCCUAGAGUCACCUUGCGUUGGAAAUCUUAAUGAUAGUGAAGGUCUCAACAGAAAACAUAUUCCAAGAAAAAAGAGGUCUGCUCUUAAGGACAUGGAGAGCUACUUGUUGAAGAUGCAGCAGAAGUUGCAAAAUGAUCUAACUGCAGAAGUAGCAGGAUCCAGCCAAACUGGACUGCACAGAAUUCCACAGUGCUCGUCCUUCUCCUCCAGCUCUUUGCACUUGCUUCUUUGCUCUAUCUGCCAACCUUUUUUUCUCAUCCUUCAGCUGCUACUAAAUAUGAACCUGGAUCCUAUAUAGCUUCUCCUCUAGGAUUUACACACAAGGAAAAUCUGAAUCAAGAUCCAGUUUUGGAAGUAACAAAAGAAUAUGCACAGAUUUUAAGAAGAAAAUACAUACUCUGAAAGAUAAGGCAAUUUUAUUUGGGCUAUUCACAUGAUAUUUUGUUUCCCAUUAAAUAUAUGAUGUGAACAUUUUUACUAAAGGGAAAUAUUCUAUAUUAUACAUGUCUGAUGAAAAUUUAUAUAGUAUUUUAAAUAAUGUUUCUUGGCCUCUUCAGCUAACUUUUAAGUGGAUUUUGCAAAUGAAAACCAGUAUUACUGAGUUUUACAUACUCGAACUGCCCAAAUGUUUGCUGUUUAAACAGCCAAAUAAUCAAGUUGCCAUUAGUAAUUUAGUGGAGCCAAUUGAUGGCUUGUUUGUAUUUUAUAAUUUUAUCUUUAUACAUAGUGAUAGAUUUAAGUUUAGAUAGACAUCAUUUUGGUAUACUGGUACUGUGGUCAUUGUCAAUGUUUGGAUGUAUUACGAUUGUUAUAGUGCAAUCAAACUUAGAUAAUUUUAAUUUUAAGCACUGAUUUAUUUAGAUCUUUCCUUGUGGAAAAAUAAGGUUUGCCUAAGGCUUUUUGCUUUUUUAUUUAUUGUUUCAUUUCUUUAUUAGAUUAACUUUUGGGAAACAGUCUUAAAAUUGGAGAAAAUUUCCACAUUUUAGGAAAAACAGCUUUCCCCCUGUGGGCCAUUUGAGAGUAAAUUGCUGACAUUAUGCCAUCACAUCUGGUAUGUGGGUAUUCCCACAAGUCAGGACAUUUUAUAUAACUACUUCAUAAUCGGAAAGUUAACAUCAAUACACUUGAUCAUUUAAUUCUCAGUUUCUUUUCAAGUUUUCUUAAUUGUCUAUAAUGUUCUUUGUAGCAGAAGGAUCCCAUUCAGGUCCAUGAAUUUCAUUUAGUUGUCAUGACUCUUUCAGUCUGGAACAGUUCCUCAGUUUUUCUUUGACCUUUAUGACCUUAAAUCUUUUGAAGAGUAAAGUCCAAUAAUACAGAAUGUCCCUCCAUUGGAUUUCUCUGAACUUUUUUUAUGAUAAGAUUUAGAUGAUAAUUUUUUUUUUGGCAAGAGUAUCACAGAAGUUAUCCCAUGAUCUUCUCACUGCAUUCUAUCAGGUGACCUGCAAUUAUUAUUAUUUUUUAUUUUCAUCUUUUAAGUUCAGGGGUACAUGUGCAGGAUGUGCAGGAUGUCCAGGUUUGUUACAUAGGUAAAUAUGUGCCAUGGUGGUUUGCUGCACAGAUCAUCCCAUCACCUAGGUAUUAAUAAUAGCCCAGCAUCCAUUAGCUGUUCUUCACGAUGCUCUCCCUUCUUUCACCCGCCACCAUCCCACAUGCCCCUGUGUGUGUUGUUCCCCGCCAUGUGUCCAUGUGUUCUCAUUAUUCAGCUCCCACUUGUAAGUGAGAGCAUGCAGUAUUUCAUUUUCUAUUUCUGCGUUGGUUUGCUGAGGAUAAUGUUCUGCAGCUCCACCCAUGUCCCUGCAAAGGACAUGUCUCAUUCCUUUUCAUGGCUGCAUAGUAUUCCAUGGUGUAUAUGUACCACAUUUUCUUUAUCCAGUUUAUCAUUGAUGGGCUUUUAGGUUGAUUCUUUGUCUUUGCUAUUGUGAAUAGUGCUGCAAUGAACAUACGUGUGCGUGUAUCUUUAUACUAGAAUUAGUUAUAUUCCUUUGGGUAUAUACCAAGUAAUGGGAUUGCUGGGUUAAAUGGUAUUUCAGGUUCUAGAUCUUUGAGGAAUCACCACACUGUCUUCCACACUGGUUGAACUAAUUUACACUCCUAUCAACAGUGUAAAAGCAUUCCUGUUUCUCCAUAAUCUUGCCAGCAUCUUUUCAUUUUUUUGAAUUAUAGCCAUUCUGACUGUUGUGAGAUGGUGUCUCAUUGUGGUUUUGAUUUGCAUUUCUCAGAUGAUCAGUGAUGUUGAAGUUUUUUUGUUUGUUGGCUGCAUGUAUGCCUUCUUUUGAAAAGUGUCUGUUUGUGUCCUUUGACCACUUUCUAAUGGGGUUGAGUUUUUUUUUCUUGUAAAUUUGUUUAAGUUCCUUGUAGAUGCUGGAUAUUAGACCUUUGUCAGAUGGAUAGAGUGCAAAAAUUUUCUCCCAUUCUGUAGGUUGUCGGUUUACUCUGUUGAUAGGUUCUUAAUGCUGUGCAGAAGCUCUUUAGUUUAAUUAGAUCCCAUUUGUCAAUUUUGGCUUUUGUUGCAAUUGCUUUUGGCAUCUUCGUCAUGAAAUCUUUGCCCUUGCCUGUGUCCUGAAUGGCAUUGCCUAGGUUUUCUUCCAGGAUUUUUAUAGUUUUGGGUUGUAGAUUUAAGUCUUUAAUCCAUCUUGAGUUAACUUUUGUAUAUGGGUUAAGGAAGGGGUCCCGUUUCAAUUUGCUGCAUAUGGCUAGCCAGUUCUCCCAGCACCAUUUAUUAAAUAGGGAAUCUUUUCCCCAUUGCUUCCUUUUGUCAGGUUUGUCAAAGAUCACAUGGUUGUAGGUGUGUGGUCUUAUUUCUGGGUUCUCUAUUCUGUUCCAUUGGUCUAUGUGUCGGUUCUUGUACCAGCACUAUGCUGUUUUGGUUACUGUAGUCUUGUAGUAUGUUUGAAGCUGGGUAGCAUGAUGCCUCUAGCUUUGCUCUUCUUGCUUAGGAUUGUCUUGGCUAUUUGGGCUCUUUUUUGGUUCCAUAUGAAUUUUAAAAUAGCUUUUUCUAGGUCUGUAAAGAAUGUGAAUAGUAGUUUAAUGGGCCUAGCAUUUAAUUUACAGAUUGCCUUGGGCAGUGUGGUCAUUUUCACGAUAUUGAACCUUCCUGUCUGUGAGCAUAUGUUUUUCCAUUUGUUUGUGUCAUCUCUGAUUUCUUUGAAUAAUGGUUUAUAGUUAUCCUUGAAAAGGUCCUUCACUUUUCUUGUUAGCUGUAUUCCUAGGUAUUAUACUCUUCUUGUGGCAAUUGUGAAUGGGAGUUAAUUCAUGAGUUUUCUCUCGGCUUGCCUGUUGUUGGUGUAUAGGAAUGCUAGUGACUUUUGCACAUUGAUUUUGUAUCCUGAGACUUUGUUGAAGUUGCUUAUCAGCUAAGAAGUUUUUGAGCUGAGAUGAUGGAGUUUUCUAGAUAUAGGAUCAUAUCAUCUGCAAACAAAGAUAGUUUGACUUCCUGUCUUCCUAUUUGAAUAGCUUUUCUUUCUUUCUCUUGCCUGAUUGCCUUGGUGAGAAUUUCUAAUACUGUGUUGAAUAGGAGUGGUGAGAGAGGGCAUCUUUGUCUUGUGUCAGUUUUCAAGGGAACGCUUCCAGGUUUUCAGGUACUCAGGCAACAAAUAGCGUUACAAUAGAAUAGUACCUCACAUCUCAAUGCUAAUGUUGAACGUAAAUGGCCUAAAUGCUCCACUUAAAAGAUAUAGAAUGGCAGAAUGGGUAAGAAUUCACCAACCAAGUUGCUGCUGUCUUCAGGAGACUCACCUAACACAUACGGACUCACAUAAACUUAAGGCAAAGGGUUGGAAAAAGACACUUCGUCUAAAUGGACACAUCAAAAGCGAGCAGGAGUAGCUGUUCUUAUAUCAGACAAAACGGACUUUAAGACAACAGCAGUUUUAAAAAGACAAAGAGGGACAUUAUAUAAUGAUAAAAGGACUAGUUCAACAGGAAAAUAUCACAGUCCUAAAUAUAUAUGCACCUAAUACUGGAGAUCCCAAAUUUAUAAAACAAUUACUACUAGACAUAAGAAAUGAGGUAGUUGGCAACACAAUAAUAGUGGGGGAUGUUAAUACUCCGCUGGCAGCACUAGGCAGAUCACCAAGACAGAAAGUCAACAAAGAAACAAUGGACUUAAACUAUACCCUGGAACAUAUGGACUUAACAGAUGCUUACAGAACAUUCUACCCAACAAGCAUAGAAUAUACAUUGUAUACAUCAGAACACGGGACAUUCUCCAAAAUAGACCAUAUGAUAGGGCACAAAACAAGUCUCAGUAAAUUUAAGAAAAUCAGAAUUAUAUCAAGUACUCUCUCAGACCACAGUGGAAUAAAAUUGGAAAUUAAUUCCAAAAGGAACACUCAAAAGCAUGCAAAUACAUGGUAAUUAAAUAACCUACUCCUGAAUGAUUGUUGGGUCAACAAUGAUAUCAAGAGGGAAAUUUAAAAAUUCUUUGAACUGAACGAUAAUAGUGACACAACCUAUCAAAAACUCUGGGAUACAGCAAAAGUGGAGCUAAGAAGAAAAUUCAUAGCAUUAAAUGCCUAUAUCAAAAAGUCUGAAAGAGCACAAAUAAACAAUCUAAGGUCACACCUCACAGAAUUGGAGAAACUAGAACAGUCCAAAUCCAAACCCAGCAGAAGAAAAGAAAUAACAAAAUCAGAACAAAACUAAAUGAAA